GCAGAACCAGCUGUCUGAGCUGCCCGGGCAGCGGGGGAGCAGCGAGCGGGCUUCCGCGAGCCGGAGAAGGCACAGGCCUGUCCCGGGUCCCGGCAGGUCAGUGUGAAGGUCUGCGCGUCUGUUCCCAGCGCUCUGCGAGGCCUAAAAAGGAGGAGCAACCUGUCCAGAAUCCCUGCAGGACAGGAAAAGGAGGGGAAAUCUCGACAUGGAAAAACCCUACAAUAAAAAUGAAGGAAACCUGGAAAACGAGGGAAAGCCAGAAGAUGAAGUAGAGCCUGAUGAUGAAGGAAAGUCAGACGAGGAAGAAAAGCCAGACGUGGAGGGGAAGACAGAAUGCGAGGGAAAGAGAGAGGAUGAGGGAGAGCCAGGUGAUGAGGGACAACUGGAAGAUGAGGGAAGCCAGGAAAAGCAGGGCAGGUCCGAAGGUGAGGGCAAGCCACAAGGCGAGGGCAAGCCAGCCUCCCAGGCAAAGCCAGAGAGCCAGCCGCGGGCCGCCGAAAAGCGCCCGGCUGAAGAUUAUGUGCCCCGGAAAGCAAAAAGAAAAACGGACAGGGGGACGGACGAUUCCCCCAAGGACUCUCAGGAGGACUUACAGGAAAGGCAUCUGAGCAGUGAGGAGAUGAUGAGAGAAUGUGGAGAUGUGUCAAGGGCUCAAGAGGAGCUAAGGAAAAAACAGAAAAUGGGUGGUUUUCAUUGGAUGCAAAGAGAUGUACAGGAUCCAUUCGCCCCAAGGGGACAACGGGGUGUCAGGGGAGUGAGGGGUGGAGGUAGGGGCCAGAGGGGCUUACACGAUAUCCCAUACCUUUAAUGCCUUUGGCCUUCCAUUCUGAUUUCUCUGAUGAGAAUAUUGCUGGCCCUGCUUUCCCUGGUAGGUAUUUGCCAGGCCCAAUGCUUUAACCUUAAGCUGAUACUUUGCUUUAGAUGUCAGUCUCGUUACCAGCAGCCUUUUGACCCAACUACGGCGCUCUAUAUUUUAGUAGAGGAUUUUCACCCAUGUGCAUGGAAAAGAUGUUCAUGGUACAUUGUAAAAAAAUAAAAUUAAAAUUAAAAAAAGUUUGCAGAACCGCA